AUCCCCGUUCCCGAUUCCUGUAGUAGCGGCUGUAUUGCAGCCGCCUGCCGAACUGACCCGGGUCUGGGGACUGGCCCCUCUGGCGCCGUUCGGUUUCUCUUAUUGCCUUCACUGAGGAUGAGUCCCUUUGUGGCUCUAUGUGGACCCUGCGGAAUCCACCGGCGCAGUUUCAUCUAGCGACUGGUCACCCUUGCAAUUAUGGAUAUUUAAAAGGGUCAGACAGUGUGGAGGGGGAGUUCCCCUCCUCACUCCCCCUUGGUGCUUGACUCCAGGAAUAAUUUAUAAACUGUGGAAUUUUUUUAAAUGAAGAACUUGUAUUUGAUAUGAACUUUAUAGAGCUAUUUAUAAUUUUUUUGAUUUAAGUGCCAAAAAAUUGUAUAAAGAUAUAUAGUUUUAUACUAUUGUCAGGAGGAUUUAAAUUAUCCUAAAAAGGUAAUUUAUUCUCUGUAACUUCCUCAAUAGCACCUUUGUGUCCUGGCUUUUUCAUUUUUUAAAAUUAGUUUUCACGAUUCUGAAGUAAGUGGUAUAAAAACAGUUAGGAUGAGUUCACCCAUGCCUGACUGCACAUCAAAGUGUCGAUCCCUGAAGCAUGCUUUGGAUGUCCUUUCUGUGGUAACAAAGGGGAGCGAAAACCAGAUUAAGGCCUUUCUCUCCAGUCAUUGUUACAAUGCUGCAACUAUCAAGGAUGUUUUUGGCAGGAAUGCCCUCCACCUUGUUUCCUCCUGUGGAAAGAAAGGAGUGUUAGAUUGGCUUAUUCAGAAAGGAGUGGAUCUGUUGGUGAAAGACAAAGAGUCUGGAUGGACAGCAUUGCACAGAAGCAUUUUUUAUGGACAUAUUGAUUGUGUUUGGUCUCUAUUGAAGCAUGGUGUUAGUCUGUAUAUUCAAGAUAAAGAAGGCUUGUCAGCUUUGGAUCUUGUAAUGAAGGAUAGACCAACUCAUGUAGUAUUCAAGAAUACUGAUCCUACAGAUGUUUAUACUUGGGGCGAUAAUACAAAUUUUACCCUGGGUCAUGGAAGCCAGAAUAGCAAACAUCAUCCAGAGUUGGUGGAUCUGUUCUCCAGGAGUGGGAUUUAUAUCAAGCAGGUGGUGCUUUGUAAAUUUCACUCCGUGUUUCUGUCUCAGAAAGGGCAGGUUUAUACCUGUGGUCAUGGUCCUGGAGGGCGAUUAGGACAUGGAGAUGAACAGACAUGCUUGGUCCCUCGGCUUGUGGAAGGACUGAAUGGUCAUAAUUGUUCCCAAGUGGCAGCUGCUAAGGAUCAUACUGUUGUAUUAACUGAAGAUGGAUGUGUUUAUACAUUUGGUCUAAACAUUUUUCAUCAAUUAGGAAUUAUUCCACCGCCUUCCAGUUGUAAUGUACCCAGACAGAUACAGGCAAAAUAUCUGAAAGGAAGGACAAUCAUUGGCGUUGCAGCAGGCAGGUUUCAUACAGUCCUAUGGACUAGAGAAGCUGUUUACACUAUGGGACUAAAUGGUGGACAACUGGGUUGUUUGCUAGAUCCCAAUGGAGAAAAGUGUGUAACUGCUCCUCGUCAGGUCUCUGCCCUUCACCAUAAAGACAUUGCUCUGUCUUUGGUUGCUGCAAGUGAUGGAGCUACAGUCUGUGUUACCACAAGGGGAGAUAUUUACUUACUUGCAGACUAUCAGUGCAAGAAGAUGGCUUCUAAACAGUUGAACUUGAAAAAAGUUCUUGUGUCUGGGGGUCAUAUGGAAUACAAGGUUGAUCCUGAACAUUUGAAAGAAAAUGGGGGUCAAAAAAUUUGCAUUCUUGCAAUGGAUGGAGCUGGAAGGGUGUUUUGCUGGAGAUCAGUCAACAGUUCUCUGAAGCAGUGUCGAUGGGCCUAUCCACGUCAGGUCUUCAUUUCUGAUAUUGCUUUAAAUAGAAAUGAAAUUCUAUUUGUUACGCAAGAUGGAGAAGGAUUUAGAGGGAGAUGGUUUGAAGAGAAAAGAAAGAGUUCUGAAAAGAAAGAGAUUUUAUCAAACCUUCACAAUUCCUCAUCAGAUGUGUCUUAUGUCUCUGAUAUAAAUAGUGUGUAUGAAAGAAUUCGACUUGAGAAACUUACCUUUGCACAUAGAGCUGUUAGUGUCAGCACAGAUCCAAGUGGAUGCAACUUUGCAAUCCUGCAGUCAGAUCCUAAAACAAGCCUUUAUGAAAUUCCAGCUGUGUCCUCAUCAUCCUUUUUUGAAGAGUUUGGCAAACUGUUGAGGGAAGCAGAUGAAAUGGACAGCAUUCAUGAUGUGACAUUUCAAGUUGGCAAUAGACUCUUCCCUGCACAUAAAUAUAUUUUGGCAGUGCAUUCUGAUUUUUUUCAGAAAUUGUUUCUUUCAGAUGGUAAUACUUCAGAAUUUACAGAUAUUUACCAGAAAGAUGAAGAUUCUGCAGGGUGCCAUCUCUUUGUGGUAGAGAAGGUUCAUCCUGACAUGUUUGAAUACCUUUUACAAUUUAUAUACACAGAUACUUGUGACUUUUUAACUCAUGGCUUCAAACCAAGAAUACACUUAAACAAAAACCCAGAAGAAUAUCAGGGAACUCUGAAUUCUCAUUUGAAUAAAGUGAAUUUCCAUGAAGAUGAUAACCAGAAGUCUGCAUUUGAAGUUUACAAAAGUAAUCAAGCUCAAACAGUUAGUGAGAGGCAGAAGAGCAAACCUAAAUCUUGUAAAAAAGGAAAAAAUAUUAGGGAAGAUGAUCCUGUAAGAAUGUUGCAAACUGUUGCAAAGAAAUUCGACUUCAGUAAUUUGAGUAGUAGGUUAGAUGGAGUCAGAUUUGAAAAUGAAAAAAUUAAUGUUAUUGCCAAGAACACUGGUAAUAAACUGAAGCUAAGUCAGAAAAAAUGUUCAUUUCUGUGUGACGUGACCAUGAAAUCAGUGGAUGGAAAGGAAUUUCCUUGUCAUAAAUGUGUUCUUUGUGCUAGACUUGAAUAUUUUCAUAGUAUGCUGAGUAGCUCAUGGAUUGAGGCUUCCAGUUGUGCAGCUCUGGAAAUGCCAAUACAUUCUGAUAUAUUAAAAGUUAUUUUGGACUACCUCUAUACUGAUGAAGCUGUGGUGAUAAAAGAAUCUCAAAAUGUAGAUUUUAUUUGUAGUGUUCUUGUGGUGGCUGAUCAACUUCUCAUAACCCGGUUGAAAGAGAUUUGUGAAGUAGCAUUAACUGAAAAACUUACCCUGAAGAAUGCUGCUAUGCUACUGGAAUUUGCAGCAAUGUAUAGUGCAAAACAGUUGAAACUGUCUUGUUUACAGUUUAUAGGAUUGAAUAUGGCAGCUUUACUUGAAGCAAGGUCUCUUGAUGUUUUAAGCGAUGGUGUUUUGAAGGAUCUUUCUGAGUUUUACCGGAAAAUGAUUCCAGCAAUGGAUAGAAGAGUCAUUACACCAUAUCAAGAUGGACCAGAUAUUAGCUAUUUGGAAGUAGAAGAUGGAGAUAUCUUCUUGAAAGAAGAAAUAAAUAUGGAACAAAAUCAUUCGGAAACUAUGUUCAAGAAAGCAAAAACAAAAGCUAAAAAGAAGCCACGUAAACGUUCAGAUAGUUCUGGAGGUUAUAACCUUUCAGAUAUUAUUCAGAGUCCAUCAUCUACAGGAUUAUUAAAGUCUGGUAAGACCAAUUCUGUGGAAUCUCUUCCAGAACUGUUGACAUCAGACUCUGAAGGAAGCUAUGCAGGAGUGGGUAGUCCUAGAGAUUUACAGUCCCCUGAUUUCACAACAGGAUUUCAUUCAGAUAAGAUUGAGGCGAAAGUCAAACCGUAUGUUAAUGGUACAUCUCCUGUGUAUUCUAGGGAAGAUUUAAAACCAUGGGAAAAGUCACCAAUACUUAAAAUAUCUGCUCCACAGCCUAUUCCCAGUAACAGAAUUGAUACUACCAGCUCUGCCAGUUGGGUUGCUGGUUCUUUCAGUCCUGUCAGCCCUCCUGUUGUGGAUCUCAGAACUAUCAUGGAAAUAGAAGAAAGUAGACAAAAAUGUGGAGCUACACCAAAGUCACAUUUAGGCAAAACAGUUUCUCAUGGAGUUAAACUUUCUCAGAAGCAACGAAAAAUGAUUGCAUUGACUACCAAGGAAAACAAUUCAGGAAUGAAUAGCAUGGAAACAGUUUUAUUCACUCCUUCAAAAGCCCCCAAACCAGUGAAUGCAUGGGCAUCUUCUCUGCAUUCAGUUUCAUCCAAGUCAUUCCGGGAUUUCUUACUAGAAGAAAAAAAGUCUGUUACUAGCCAUAGUUCAGGCGAUCAUGUCAAAAAAGUUUCUUUUAAAGGAAUUGAAAAUUCUCAGGCACCAAAAAUUGUCAGAUGGAGUUUCGUUCUUGUUGCCCAGGCUGGAGUGCAAUGGCUUGAUCUCAGCUCACCGCAACCUCUGCCUCCUGGGUUCAAGCGAUUCUCCUGCCUCCGCCACCCUAGUAGCUGGGAUUACAGAUGCUCUACCCAUGGUACCCCAGGACCAGAAGGCAACCAUAUUUCAGAUUUACCACUUCUAGACAGUCCCAAUCCCUGGCUAUCUUCUUCAGUGACUGCUCCAUCCAUGGUAGCCCCAGUCACUUUUGCAUCUAUUGUAGAAGAAGAACUACAACAAGAAGCAGCUCUUAUUAGAAGUCGAGAAAAACCGUUGGCUCUGAUUCAGAUUGAGGAGCAUGCCAUACAAGAUUUAUUGGUUUUCUAUGAGGCAUUUGGCAACCCUGAAGAGUUUGUCAUUGUUGAAAGGACACCGCAGGGACCACUGGCAGUACCUAUGUGGAAUAAGCAUGGAUGCUAGUUCACUGUGGAGUUGAGAUGCAUUUUACAUAAUUAUGAGUUUGUUCAUAUAAAGAAAAGCUGUGGAAAAGAGUCUUAGAGAUUUUGUAAUAUCAUUCUAAAUAGAUUAAGAAAAGAUAUAAUUUCUUUACUGCAGUUAAAUCAUAUAAUGUUUGUAUGAUUAAAAAUAAAUUUCUCAGAAUUGUGAUUUUAGUAACUUUAUAUAAAAUGUGUGAGACAAAAACUUAUUAAGGUUAAAUAGAAUUGUUUCUUCUGAAUAAUCUAACAAAGGAAAAUAUAAGUGAUUGAAUCAUAAGAUAUAAGGGGGGUAAAGUAUUAAAAAUAACUUUUUUGUUUGAUAACUUGAGAAUUUAGAAGAUUUUGCCAAGUAUGUGUUGUUGCUUGACUUCUUAAAUAUGGCAUUGAUGAAUUUAAAGUAGGAGCAUCAGUUAUUACUUCUGAUUCAUUAAUGGCCAGAAUUUUGUGUUUGGUGUAAUAGUUGUGUCACCAUUCUUGUUGCUUUUUAAAAAUCAGGCUAAUCAUGUGGUCCAUGUCUCUUCAAAGCUUGACCUGCACAAAUGCCAUAUUUCUAUUUGGACCACAUAUUCUCCAUUUUGCAUUGAGCAGUAGAGUACAGUGGAAAGGGAAUAAGAAUACUGAUUAUUCUGAACAGUUUAGUCCCAAGAGAAUAGCGUUUUAAAAAAGAAAAACAAGAUUUGGAGUCAUUGUGGGUUAUUUUUGGUGGGAUGGAGGAUCUUAAAAAUGCCUAAUUGUGAGAGAAUCAAUUGCUGAAAGUGUUAAAAUUUCUGAAAAUAAAUGCUUAAUUACAUAUACAGGAAUUAAAUAGUUUGGAAGAGGGUUGGAUUAUCAUUACCUUUACAAUACUGUAUAAUCAGAAGUUCUCUGAACCUCAAUUGUAUAUCUAGACAUAAAAAUUGUUUUCUGUAUAGGAUGUUGUUUGGUUUGUUUCUGAGUGUUUAAAUUUUGCAAAAACAAAUGUUAAAUUUGUGCUUCAGUACCUAGAUAAAUUGGAAAGGUUAAUGUUCUAGUUUCUGGAAGGUAAGCCUGGGAGACACAUAAGCAAUUCACUGCUAUAAUUUAGUUGAUGUAAAAUGACGGAAACUGACUCAAUAUGUCAGGUUUAACUCUGCCCAAAAGCAGCAGACAUGUAAGCAGAUGUGCAAUAAAAAAUGAUCUUGAUCCAUUUCACUAAUGUGUGCUUGACAUUUUUUACUAUAUUGACAUUUAUUAUGGAAAGAGUUAAUAAUUAUUUUUUCUGAUGUGCUACACUAGUGGCCAGUAUAUGGUUAAGUUGAUGCUGUAUUUAUUCUAAGACGGAUUUAAAAAGGCAGUUUUCUAAAUAUGAACUUGUGAAUUUUUGUAUGUGUGUUUGAGUAAAUUGAGAAAUGAAUUUUAUAAAUGUUCUAUUGAUGUUGCAGUAAAGAAGCCUUUUGAAGUAA